AAUGUCCACCACCACCCUGUUCCCACAUUAUCCGUAAGUCUUGCUAAAGGCAAGAUUGCUGUUUUCUGGAAUUUUCAAAGACAGACAGUUGGACUACCUGCAGUCAUCUGGAAUUUGGCCAGAACAAAGGAAGUAAGCAAAUAGAAGACUCCCAAAUAAGGUAUAUAUUUAUCAUCAAAGCAGAUGCCCAAGCCUGUUUACCUCACUCAGAGGAGGCGCCCACGGCAACUAUGAACUCUUACUUUACACAGAGUCCUUGCACGCUGGGUUCUGCUGGUGUCCAAGUCCUCAGAGGCUUUGAAGUAGCAAAUUGUGUUGGUGGGAUGGAGCCGCCAUCAGCCCCAUGUUGGACUGUUGGCAGCCUGGGACCGUGUAGAACCACAGAUGUGGACACAAGCAUUUUUCCUUUCCUUUCUCUUUUUCUCUUUCUCUCUCUCUUUUUUUUUUUUUUUUUUUUUGCAGAUUGUAAGAAAGGAGAGGGGAAUAUGGGAAUUUAUUUAUUUAUUUACUUAUUUAUUUAUUUUGAGACAGUGUCUUGCUCUGUUGCCUAGGCUGGAGUGCAGUGGUGCGAUCUCAGCUCACUGCAACCUCCACCUCCCAGGUUCAAGCAAUUCUCAUGCCUUAGCCUCUGGAGUAACUGGGACUACAGGCAUGCACCACCUUGCCCAGCUAAUUUUUGGAUUUUUAGUAGAGAUGGGGUUUCACCAUGUUGGCCAGGCUGGUCUCGAACUCCUGACCUCAAGUGAUUCACCCGCCUCGGCCUCCCAAAGCACUGGGAUUACAGGCAUGAGCCACCGUGCCCAGCUGGGAUCGAUUUUAGAAAAAGAUUAAGGCUGAGUGCAGUGGCUUAUGCCUGUAAUCCCAACGCUUUGGGAGGAUCACUUGAGGCCAGCCUGGGCAACAUAGUGAGACCCCGUCUCUACAAAAAAUUAAAAAUUAAAAAAACUAGCUAAUCAUGGUGGCAUGUGCCUGGAGUCCCAGCUGGUCGAGAGGCUGAAGUGGGAGGAUCACUCGAACCCAGGAGUUCAAGGCUGUAGUAAGCUAUGAUUGCGCCACUGCACUGCAGCCUUGGCAACACAGCGAGACCCCGAUUGUAAAACAAAGUUCAGUUUAAGAAAGAAAAAAGAAAAGAAAAAGGUUAAGAUACUUUUUUCGGGGGAAUGUUUACAGAGGCUGUGGGUCAGAAUGAAGCAACACCAGAAGCUAUGGAGACUGGGGUUUCUGCUGUGUUUCAACUUGGUUUUUUGUGUUCUCGGGAGAAGACACCCUUGGCCGUGGGCCGUGAGACCUUUGAUGUGUGUUUACGCUGACCGCGAGUUGUUGGGAUGGCUUCUGCGGUGGGUGGUUCUCUUGGUAUUCUCGGUUUUGAAGCUUAUUUUUAGACUCUGAACUCUCCUUCUUGGCAGGAGUUGAAUCCCCCUGGGGGUUUUCAAGUUGUUCUUGGACUGCUGGUUUUUGAAAUAGAAGCCCCUUUGGUGGGGUCCCCCAUAAACCCAGGCGCUGGUGCCCACCUUGUGAUGUGAAGGCUCCUGUAACACGACCUCACUUUCCUGGCCCCGCACUACUCACCUGCCCCACGGGACACAGGUAAAAUGUCGGUUCCAGGACCUUACCAGGCGGCCACUGGGCCUUCCUCAGCACCAUCCGCACCUCCAUCCUAUGAAGAGACAGUGGCUGUUAACAGUUAUUACCCCACACCUCCAGCUCCCAUGCCUGGGCCAACUACGGGGCUUGUGACGGGGCCUGAUGGGAAGGGCAUGAAUCCUCCUUCGUAUUAUACCCAGCCAGCGCCCAUCCCCAAUAACAAUCCAAUUACCGUGCAGACGGUCUACGUGCAGCACCCCAUCACCUUUUUGGACCGCCCUAUCCAAAUGUGUUGUCCUUCCUGCAACAAGAUGAUCGUGAGUCAGCUGUCCUAUAACGCCGGUGCUCUGACCUGGCUGUCCUGCGGGAGCCUGUGCCUGCUGGGGUGCAUAGCGGGCUGCUGCUUCAUCCCCUUCUGCGUGGAUGCCCUGCAGGACGUGGACCAUUACUGUCCCAACUGCAGAGCUCUCCUGGGCACCUACAAGCGUUUGUAGGACUCAGCCAGACGUGGAGGGAGCCGGGUGCCGCAGGAAGUCCUUUCCACCUCUCAUCCAGCUUCACGCCUGGUGGAGGUUCUGCCCUGGUGGUCUCACCUCUCCAGGGGGCCCACCUUCAUGUCUUCUUUUGGGGGGAAUACGUCGCAAAACUAACAAAUCUCCAAACCCCAGAAAUUGCUGCUUGGAGUCGUGCAUAGGACUUGCAAAGACAUUCCCCUUGAGUGUCAGUUCCACGGUUUCCUGCCUCCCUGAGACCCUGAGUCCUGCCAUCUAACUGUGAUCAUUGCCCUAUCCGAAUAUCUUCCUGUGAUCUGCCAUCAGUGGCUCUUUUUUCCUGCUUCCAUGGGCCUUUCUGGUGGCAGUCUCAAACUGAGAAGCCACAGUUGCCUUAUUUUUGAGGCUGUUCUGCCCAGAGCUCGGCUGAACCAGCCUUUAGUGCCUACCAUUAUCUUAUCCGUCUCUUCCCGUCCCUGAUGACAAAGAUCUUGCCUUACAGACUUUACAGGCUUGGCUUUGAGAUUCUGUAACUGCAGACUUCAUUAGCACACAGAUUCACUUUAAUUUCUUAAUUUUUUUUUUAAAUACAAGGAGGGGGCUAUUAACACCCAGUACAGACAUAUCCACAAGGUCGUAAAUGCAUGCUAGAAAAAUAGGGCUGGAUCUUAUCACUGCCCUGUCUCCCCUUGUUUCUCUGUGCCAGAUCUUCAGUGCCCCUUUCCAUACAGGGAUUUUUUUCUCAUAGAGUAAUUAUAUGAACAGUUUUUAUGACCUCCUUUUGGUCUGAAAUACUUUUGAACAGAAUUUCUUUUUUUUAAAAAAAAACAGAGAUGGGGUCUUACUAUGUUGCCCAGGCUGGUGUCGAACUCCUGGGCUCAAGCGAUCCUUCUGCCUUGGCCUCCCGAAGUGCUGGGAUUGCAGGCAUAAGCUACCAUGCUGGGCCUGAACAUAAUUUCAAGAGGAGGAUUUAUAAAACCAUUUUCUGUAAUCAAAUGAUUGGUGUCAUUUUCCCAUUUGCCAAUGUAGUCUCACUUAAAAAAAAAAAAAAGAAAAAGAAAUGGAUAAUUUCAUCUACUGCCUUUACUUGGGGUUAAUGUGAUUCUUAAACACCUUCAUCAUGGAACUCUCAGAGUGGGGUCCGUUUUGGUUUCCUGGUGGUGGGUUUUGAAAGAUAAGGGAAAGCACAUUUUGAGCAUGUCUGGGUACCAUGGUGCGGAUGCUUGGGAACCAGAACUGUUUCAGAGGAAUCUAAAGUCUGAUUUUAGUUUUCAGAGACACAGCUUGUUGUAAAACAUGAGAAGACAUGAUUUCUAGGACUCAAGCAGCAAGCCAGGAUUCUAGGUUGGCUGCUGUGUCAUCUUUGAAGUCAAGACAAAGCUGGGCUCGACCUUCAAGGGUCCUCGUUUUGAUAAUACUUCAGAAUAGGGAACUCAUGUGAAUACUACUAUGUAGAAAUAAAACCUAGACCUUGAGCGAACAUCUGUAUAUUGGUUGAAAACGAUAGUGGUAACCAUUGAUCCCCCUUCAUUUGAUGUUUGGAAAAUUCCAGUAAUUAUCAUUUUUGCAACGAAUAUGGAUACCACAUAGUACUUUGGUGUUACCUGCUUUUGAAAAAUAAAGUCUUUGGUUCACCCGGUGAACUAUUUAUGAGUUCUUUUGGUGUGAAGAAAGGGCUCAUGUUGCAUUUCCAGCCAUUGCUACAAAGAACCUUUAUUUGUUCAGUAACGGUAGAAAAUCCUUCCCGAUUAAAAACUUCAGACUUGCUGAAUAUCCUGCAAUGUCAAGAUGACCGAUGUUGAGUUGGGUGGAUUUGCUAACGAGUCAGAUUUGAACAUGAGGCUAUUGGAACCCAAUAGGCGUCAUUGAUGGCGGCAAGCCAUAGCUUUCAAGUUUUAAUAAAAUGCACAAAAGAGAA